AGGCAGAGUCUCGCUGUGUCCCCCAGGCUGGAGUGCAAUGGCAGGAUCUCGGCUCACUGCAACCUCUACCUCCCUGCAACCUCUACCUACCUGGUUCAAGCGAUUAUCCAGCCUUACCCUCCUGAGUAGCUGGGACUACAGGCAUGCGCCACCACGCCUGGCUACUUUUUGUAUUUUUAGUAGAGACGGGGUUUCACCAUAUUGGCCAGGCUGGUCUUGAACUCCUGACUUCGUGAUCUGCCUGCCUCGGCUUCCCAAAGUGUUGGGAUUACAGGCGUGAGCCACCGUGUCCGGCCUUGAGAUAUUUUUUUAAUUCAAAAGUUUAUUCACAAACUUCAACUUUUAAGUGUUUUAUUACAGAUAGACUGGUAAGCUACAGAAUUUUUAGGACUUUUUUUUUGGGGGGGCGGGCUAGGAGGGCUGAUUUCUGAGAAGCAGAGAAAAACUUGUAGACAGGAGAAGCCGUUUCUGUUACAGUAAAAUAAAGCUAUUAUACUAUUAGUAUCCUUCAUGAUAUUAAGCAGAUACAAGACCCGUUCUUAUUUAUUAAAAGAACUGAGGGAUAUAGUAAGUAUCAGUUUUUAUUAAAGCUGUCUUUCUCCUAUUGGACAAUGAGUUGCGUUUACUGAGGGCCAGAAUCCUUUUGCUCAUAUCAGGUUUGCUCCUGCCUAGCAUAUAGUAGUUGCUCAAUAUAUGUUUAUAUAUUAAACGAAUAAAUUGGUGGCUUUAUUCUUUCUGCCUAAAAUAUUGUCUGGUCUUAUUUGUUAGGAAUUCUGACCACCUGAUUUUCCAUAAUGCCUCAUAUCUGGUAUUCUGGGUACUCUGCAAUUAGGCCAUUAAGAAACUGAAAGAACCAAGUUGCAUUUUUUUUUUUCCAGGCUGGCUAGGGAACCAUCUACUGGAGUUGAGGCUAUUUUUUCCUGCCCUUUUAUAGGAUAUUUUUUAAAGUAUGAAAUAUUUUAAGUGUACAGAGAUCAAUAUAAUGAACCUUCAUAUACAUACCACCCAGCUCUAUAAGAUUCUAGUAAUCUGCCAUGUUUGUUAUUUUAAAAUAAAUAACACAUUAAAACGCAGAUAAAUGAUUCUGGUCUCUUUCCUUAAUCUCCGGGUAAUCAUUAUGAAUUUGGUAUUUGUCUCAUUUUUUUUUCCUUUUUUUUUUUUUUUUAGUUUUGCAAUAUACAUAUGUACUUACCAAAAAAAACUAUUUUGCAUGCAUAUAACUACUUAUCUGUUCUCCUAUUUUAUGAAGUUGAGGUUGUUUCUAAUUUUCUUUACCAAAAAAAAAUGAGCAUUUCUCUAGGGAGUUUACUGUGAAGAAAAAUGGCCGGGUCAUAGAGUACGCUAUUUAUUUAUUCAUUUAUAUGUUUAUGCCAAAUUGCUCUGAAGUUUUUACUAAUUUAAACUCCAACCACUAUUGUGUGAAAGUUUGUUUUUCUACACUCCUCAGACUUGACAUUAACAGAGAUGCAUGUUUUUUCAAUCUGAAAUGUUCUCUUAAGGUAAUCUUUUCCUAUCAGUCACAUUAAAUACCUUUUCAUAGGUAUUAUUCAUUGUUCAAGUUUACUCUUAUAAGUUGAAGAACAUUAUUUGCAUAUUUGUGCUGUUAGAUUUUUGUUCAUUGGAUAUUGAUAGGCAUAGUUAAUAAGUAAACAUGCUUUUUAACAAACUAACACAUUGCAGGCUUCUUCUAUAUUCUUUUAGAUAUUUAGAUAGAUGUUACUAACGUUUUACCCCUCACAAAACUCAAGUUCUAUAAAAAUAUUAUGAACCUUCCCAUACUUGUUGGCAUUUCAGAAAUGGUACAACCUAAUGAGCCUGUUACCAAGAAUCUAGUGUAGUGAAAUCUGGAGCCCGGGCCAACGUGUGUGAAUUGCUGAUAACAUUUUUGUUGUAUCAGAGUAAGAUGGACGGUAGCUUUGAUUGUGAUUGUGGUGAGCUGGAGCCACCUGAUCACUAACAAAAGACAUCUUCUGUUAACCAACAGCCGCCAGGGCUUCCUGUUGAAAUAAAUAUAUAGCAACAAAGGAAAAAAAGAAGCAAAACGGAAAUAGUGCUUACCAGCACCUUAGAAUGAUGCUGCUCAGGACCAGUCCAACACUGAAUGUAUCUGCACUGUGAGGAGAAUGUUCAUAGAAGCCUGUUGUGUGCAUAUUUAUUCACAUUUUUGUUAAAUGUUAAAUCGUUUAGCACGGUAAUCUGAGUGCACAGUAUGUCAUUUCAUUCCGUUUGAGUUUCUUGUUUUCGUUAAAUGUCUGCAGAGUUGCUGCCCCUUUCUUGAACUAUGAGUACUGCAAUCUUUUUAAUUCUCAAUAUGAAUAGAGCUUUUUGAGCUUUAAAUCUAAGGGGAACUCGACAGGCCUGUUUGGCAUAUGCAAUGAACAUCAAGAAACCAUCUUGCUGUGGAAGCAUAAUUAUUUUUCUUCUCCCUUUUUGAAAGAUCUUUCCUUUUGAUGCCAGUUUUCUUCCUUGUUUACACAAGUUCAAUUUGAAAGGAAAAGGCAAUAGUAAGGGUUUCAAAAUGGCAGAGAAAUUUGAAAGUCUCAUGAACAUUCAUGGUUUUGAUCUGGGUUCUAGGUAUAUGGACUUAAAACCAUUGGGUUGUGGAGGCAAUGGCUUGGUUUUUUCUGCUGUAGACAAUGACUGUGACAAAAGAGUAGCCAUCAAGAAAAUUGUCCUUACUGAUCCCCAGAGUGUCAAACAUGCUCUACGUGAAAUCAAAAUUAUUAGAAGACUUGACCAUGAUAACAUUGUGAAAGUGUUUGAGAUUCUUGGUCCCAGUGGAAGCCAAUUAACAGACGAUGUGGGCUCUCUUACGGAACUGAACAGUGUUUACAUUGUUCAGGAGUACAUGGAGACAGACUUGGCUAAUGUGCUGGAGCAGGGCCCUUUACUGGAAGAGCAUGCCAGGCUUUUCAUGUAUCAGCUGCUACGGGGGCUCAAGUAUAUUCACUCUGCAAAUGUACUGCACAGAGAUCUCAAACCAGCUAAUCUUUUCAUUAAUACGGAAGACUUGGUGCUGAAGAUAGGUGACUUUGGUCUUGCACGGAUCAUGGAUCCUCAUUAUUCCCAUAAGGGUCAUCUUUCUGAAGGAUUGGUUACUAAAUGGUACAGAUCUCCACGUCUUUUACUUUCUCCUAAUAAUUAUACUAAAGCCAUUGACAUGUGGGCUGCAGGCUGCAUCUUUGCUGAAAUGCUGACUGGUAAAACCCUUUUUGCAGGUGCACAUGAACUUGAACAGAUGCAGCUGAUUUUAGAAUCUAUUCCUGUUGUACAUGAGGAAGAUCGUCAGGAGCUUCUCAGCGUAAUUCCAGUUUACAUUAGAAAUGACAUGACUGAGCCACACAAACCUUUAACUCAGCUGCUUCCAGGAAUUAGUCGAGAAGCACUGGAUUUCCUGGAACAAAUUUUGACAUUUAGCCCCAUGGAUCGGUUAACAGCAGAAGAAGCACUCUCCCAUCCUUACAUGAGCAUAUAUUCUUUUCCAAUGGAUGAGCCAAUUUCAAGCCAUCCUUUUCAUAUUGAAGAUGAAGUUGAUGAUAUUUUGCUUAUGGAUGAAACUCACAGUCACAUUUAUAACUGGGAAAGGUAUCAUGAUUGUCAGUUUUCAGAGCAUGAUUGGCCUGUACAUAACAACUUUGAUAUUGAUGAAGUUCAGCUUGAUCCAAGAGCUCUGUCCGAUGUCACUGAUGAAGAAGAAGUACAAGUUGAUCCCCGAAAAUAUUUGGAUGGAGAUCGGGAAAAGUAUCUGGAGGAUCCUGCUUUUGAUACCAAUUACUCUACUGAGCCUUGUUGGCAAUACUCAGAUCAUCAUGAAAACAAAUAUUGUGAUCUGGAGUGUAGCCAUACUUGUAACUACAAAACGAGGUCAUCAUCAUAUUUAGAUAACUUAGUUUGGAGAGAGAGUGAAGUUAACCAUUACUAUGAACCCAAGCUUAUUAUAGAUCUUUCCAAUUGGAAAGAACAAAGCAAAGAAAAAUCUGAUAAGAAAGGCAAAUCAAAAUGUGAAAGGAAUGGAUUGGUUAAAGCCCAGAUAGCGCUAGAGGAAGCAUCACAGCAACUGGCUGGAAAAGAAAGGGAAAAGAAUCAGGGAUUUGAUUUUGAUUCCUUUAUUGCAGGAACUAUUCAGCUUAGUUCCCAGCAUGAGCCUACUGAUGUUGUUGAUAAAUUAAAUGACUUGAAUAGCUCAGUGUCCCAACUAGAAUUGAAAAGUUUGAUAUCAAAGUCAGUAAGCCAAGAAAAACAGGAAAAAGGAAUGGCAAAUCUGGCUCAAUUAGAAGCCUUGUACCAGUCUUCUUGGGACAGCCAGUUUGUGAGUGGUGGGGAGGACUGUUUUUUCAUAAAUCAGUUUUGUGAGGUAAGGAAGGAUGAACAAGUUGAGAAGGAAAACACUUACACUAGUUACUUGGACAAGUUCUUUAGCAGGAAAGAAGAUACUGAAAUGCUAGAAACUGAGCCAGUAGAGGAUGGGAAGCUUGGGGAGAGAGGACAUGAGGAAGGAUUUCUGAACAACAGUGGGGAGUUCCUCUUUAACAAGCAGCUCGAGUCCAUAGGCAUCCCACAGUUUCACAGUCCAGUUGGGUCACCACUUAAGUCAAUACAGGCCACAUUAACACCUUCUGCUAUGAAAUCUUCCCCUCAAAUUCCUCAUCAAACAUACAGCAGCAUUCUGAAACAUCUGAACUAAAACACUCAGCAGACAUUUAUCUUUGUAUUCUUCAUGAAAUGUGUUUUGUCUUUUUUUAUUACUAGUGUUUAAGUCAUUUUUUACUUGAAUCAGAUGGUGUCAUUUAGUAAGGAUUUUAUGAGUUCUUGUUUUUUAAAAUCCAGACUUUCUUUUUCUACAUGUGAGAUAGUUUUCAUUUUAACUGGCAUGUCAUUUGCACACAAAAAUAAAGACUAGAGCAAAAUAAUGCAACGCAGGAGGAGAAAAGAAAUGCACUAAGACAAGAACAUUCUCUCAUAGAACAUUGAUCUGUUUUACAGGAAACAAACCUUGCCUUGAAAUUUACACAGUGAGACUGUACAUAAUUGCAUGAAAAUAGCUAUUUUUUUCCUAAGACAUUUUUCAUUCAUGAAUAUUUUCAAGUUUUUCAUACUGUACACAUUUCUUAAAACACAUGAUACCAGCAGCAACUGAAAAUGAAUGCCGAAUUUGGUACACAUGUGUUAUCUACCUCAAGGUAACAAGAGUAUGUGGCAAAACAUAUACCACCCAUAGUGCUUCACAAAAUGCACUUCUAUUUAGCCAGCGUUUAUUGUAGUAAACUAUUCUUAAUAAAACUCACUCACUGUUUAUAAAUGUUCUGGUAUGCAUUCUUUAUAGUGAAGUGUUAAUACAUCACAUCUUAUUUAUUUUAGCAAAUCAGUAUAUUUUCUGUAUUUAAUUAUAAAAAAUUAACUUAGUUUUUAAAAUUUAUUUGCAAAUAUACUUUACUUUUUCCAUUUGGCACUAUGGUUUGUUGCCUACCUAGCUGCAUCUAUAAUGUCAGCUUAUCCUAAGGCUGUCCACGUACUUAAUUUACUUAAGUGUUCAUUUUAAGUAACGUGCUCACUGUGUAUAGGAAUUUGUAUUUUGGAGGUGCUUGAUCUAUCUACAAAGAAAAAUUAAUUAGGAAUUACUUUAUUAUAAAAUGCUCCUAGAAGUCUUAAUUGUGUUUAUUUUUUAAAAAAACAAAUGUUAGACUUGUGUGCAUGGAAGUAAUUAAGGUACAUCAUUAUUGUAGUUUGAAAGUUGUACAUGAUAAGACAUUUUGUUUUUACUGUAUGUUUUUACUGAAUGAUCUAUUCCCCAUCCCAAGGCAAGCAUGAAUAAAAUUAGGUUAAACGUAGCAUGUGGCAUCGCAGUCUCUUAGAAUUUGUUUCAUCUAUUUUAUUUUAUUGAAUACUGUCUGUAUCUUUGGUUAUCCUGUUUGAAGAAAAAGGACAAAUAAAACAUGGCCAGCAAAUACAGCUCCUGUUUCACUCUUGGGUUAAUGAAAAUUUUCUGCUAGAAUGAAAAUUACUACCAGAAUCACUUUGAAUUAUGGCCAUAAAUUGCUAGUCUGAAAGGCUGAGAAGGUUCAAGUCUUUUGACUUAAACCAUCACAUAUUAGAAUGGAAUAAAGCUUUAUAAUAUUUCAAAACUGUUAGGUAAAAUGUGUAGUUGAAACUUUGAACUGUGCAGUCAGAAAACUUGAGAUUUGCUCUGUAAUACAUCUUUGCGUAAGAACUUACCCUUUUACCUAUCCAGCUACAAAACCAUCCUCUUCACCUCACUUUUCUUUCAUCCUUGUUUUGUACAACACCAAUUCUAUUAAUAUCUGCCCACCUACCUUCUCAACAACUCCAUCCUCUUCACCUCACUUUUCUUUCAUCCUUGUUUUGUACAACACCAAUUCUAUUAAUAUCUGCCCACCUACCUUCUCAACAACUGACUUCAUCUGGAUUCACAAAGCCAUAUAUAUACACGUGUGUGUGUGUGUGUGUGUGUGUGUGUGUAUAUAUAUUCAUUUAUUUAUUUUCUGGUUGAAUACUGUCACGUUAUUAAUUUAAACAUACUCAAAUUACCUUAAGAGGACAAGCUCUGAAGUGCAGUCAUGAGAAUUGAUUUGUGGGGAAAAAAAAAAUGGGACACUUUUAGUUGGAGCUGGGUGGGGUGACAAGUGCAGAGGCUUUGAGUGUCAUGAGAGCAUCAGACAGGAUGUAAAGGAAGCAACGGGCAGCAGACAUUGGUCCCUGAUCCUCCAUUAUAACCAAUUUUUUGCAAACGUAUGUUGAUUUUGAGAAUAAUUAGCUUUGACUCUAAAAUGCUGUCUUCCCUGAAGGAGACCUAGGAUUUUUCUUACUGGGAAACUUGGCUCCUGGACUUAAUCCACAUUCGUUAAACUGUCACCUUGGCAGUUUAGUGGCCAUCUACACAAUGAUCUGACUUGUUGGCAUUAAAAAGUCCAAACAUAGUCAUCAAAGGAAGAAGAAAGUAAAACUGAAACCCCUUAUAUAAAAUAUGCUUGCUUUAGGGUGACCCAGGCUGAGUACUAAGUUGUAAAGUCAAUUUCCAAUAAAAAUUUUAUGUGCCAAUUA